GAGCCAGGCCAGCAGCCCUAGCUUCUGGAAGGAUCCUUCAGGCUCCAGACACCCAACCUACCCGUGGCCGGAUGUCUGCCUGAGCCCCACCCCGAAUGCCAGCCCUUCUUCCCUGAGCUCACCCAGCCCCAGCUCCAGGACUGAGAGCCCCAGGAAGCUUGGAGAGGUGUGAGAGAGACAGGUGUCCAGCCUCAGCCCCGAUCCUUCACCUGCAGAGCCCGGCAUGUGGGGCUACCUGUCGCUGAUGCCUGUCUUCCUAGCUGUCUGGGCUAUCUCUGGCGUCUGGAUCGUUUUUGCCAUUGCAGUGACCAACAGGACUGUGGACCUCAGUAAAGGCUUUCCCUACAUCAGCAUCUGCGGAUCCUUCCCCCCUCAGAGCUGCAUCUUCAGCCAGGUGCUCAAUAUGGGAGCUGCUCUGGCCGCGUGGAUCUGCAUUGUCCGUUACCACCAGCUCCGGGACUGGGGCGUCAGAAGGUGGCCUAACCAGCUGAUCCUAUGGACGGGUCUUCUGUGUGCCCUGGGCACCUCCGUGGUAGGCAAUUUCCAGGAAAAGAACCAGCGGCCUACGCACUUGGCAGGGGCCUUCCUUGCCUUCAUCUUGGGUAACGUCUACUUCUGGCUGCAGCUCCUCCUGUGGAGGCUGAAGAGGCUGCCCCAGCCCGGGGCUGCCUGGAUUGGGCCCCUCCGCCUGGGCCUCUGCAGCGUCUGCACCAUCCUCAUUGUGGCCAGAACUGGAACACACAAGGAAACAGUCUCUGCCAGAGAGCCUCCAGGUGCAGCCCUCCAGGCACCCUGUUAGCCUGCAGAGACCAUGUGGGACUUCUGACCUCCAGGACUGUACGAAAAUCACUUGUGUUGUUUCAGCCACCAAGGCUGUGUCAUUUGUUGACGGCGGCCAUAGAAAACAAACACGGGGUGAAACCAGCUCCCCUAGUUGAGAACCACGGCUCCAGAGCAAAAGACCUGACCCUGGGACUCAGAGUUUCUGGUGACAAGGCCAAAGCUGCCCUGGCUCCUGGCCUCAACGCUGGGCCGUUUCCUUUCAACGGGGUCCAGGGGUCCAGGAAGGGGCAUGGGUCCUGUGAGGCUGAUGCUGCCUGACUCCCCUCAGAGCAGACGGCUGUCCACGUGCCCUGCAAUGGGGCCCAGUACCCUGUUUCACUGUGUCCCCUGUGACCCCGUGUCUCAGGAAUGAGGGCUGAUUUCCAGGGCAGGCGCUCUCUUCCCUUGAGAAUUCUGGCUACCUCUGGUUGCUUGGGCGAGUGCCCCUUAUGCUCUCUACUGAACACUGCAUCCUCCCAAAUUCAUGUGCUGAAACCCAAUCCCAAGGUGAUGGUAUUAGGAGGUUAUGUUAGGAGGUGAUGAGGUCAUGAGGGUGGGGCCUUCAUGAAUGGGAUUAGUGUCCUUAGGAAAGAGGCCCCAGAGAGUUCCCUUGCCCCUUCUGCCAUGUGAAGACACAGCACCAACGUGCUGUCUGUGACCCAGGAAGCAGCUCUCACCAGGCACCAACGCUGCUGGCAGCUUGAUCUUGGACUUCCCAGCCUCCAGAAUUGUCAGCAAUAAAUUUCUGUUAUUUGUAA